AUACAGGCCCCCACCAUGAAGGGUUUCACAGCCACUCUCUUCCUCUGGACUCUGAUUUUUCCCAGCUGCAGUGGAGGCGGCGGUGGGAAAGCCUGGCCCACACACGUGGUCUGUAGCGACAGCGGCUUGGAAGUGCUCUACCAGAGUUGCGAUCCAUUACAAGAUUUUGGCUUUUCUGUUGAAAAGUGUUCCAAGCAAUUAAAAUCAAAUAUCAACAUUAGAUUUGGAAUUAUUCUGAGAGAGGACAUCAAAGAGCUUUUUCUUGACCUAGCUCUCAUGUCUCAAGGCUCAUCUGUUUUGAAUUUCUCCUAUCCCAUCUGUGAGGCGGCUCUGCCCAAGUUUUCUUUCUGUGGAAGAAGGAAAGGAGAGCAGAUUUACUAUGCUGGGCCUGUCAAUAAUCCUGAAUUUACUAUUCCUCAGGGAGAAUACCAGGUUUUGCUGGAACUGUACACUGAAAAACGGUCCACCGUGGCCUGUGCCAAUGCUACUAUCAUGUGCUCCUGACUGUGGCCUGUAGCAAAAAUCACAGCCAGCUGCAUCUCGUGGGACCUCCAAGCUCCUCUGACUGAACCUACUGUGGGAGGAGAAGCAGCUGAUGACAGAGAGAGGCUCUACAAAGAAGCGCCCCCAAAGAGUGCAGCUGCUAAUUUUAGUCCCAGGACCAGACAUCCCCAGACUCCACAGAUGUAAUGAAGUCCCCGAAUGUAUCUGUUUCUAAGGAGCCUCUUGGCAGUCCUUAAGCAGUCUUGAGGGUCCAUCCUUUUUCUCUAAUUGGUCGCCUCCCACCAGACUCACCUGCUUUUCAACUUUUUAGGAGUGCUUCCUCACAGUUACCAAGAAUAAAGAAAGCUGGCCACCA